GCAAGCAGGCCAAGCCCCACUCCUCAAGAUGGAGGAGGAGCUGCUGCUCCCGGUGGGGACUCCCCAGUAGGCCACUGGGGGAAGCCCCACGACCCAGACAGCAGGUGGAGAGCAGCAGCUGGCCGGAGAUCGACUUCAGCGAGAAACUGUGCGGAGCUCCAGCAGCUGGACUUCCUGGAGCAGAAGAGCCGCUGAACCCCGCCCCUGCUGAUCUCACUGCACACAGCCUAGGGCCCCACCCGCCGAGGACUCCAGAACCUUCUCCUACCAGCUCGCCCAGAGACCAAGCCAAGAGAGUGGUCUCUGAGGAGCCCGCUAGAAAGGCAAGGCGAGGCCCGCAGAGAAGGAUGCCAAGCCUGUAGAAGCAGAGACGUCGGGGAUGGGGGACCUGCCCUGGGCGCCGCCAGAGGCCCAAGCGCCCAGCACCGCAGGAGCUGGAGACGUCGCUGAGCACCAGGUGGCGCCGGCGCGGUUCCUACAGGGAGCCUGGAGGCAGGCUGCGGGGUGGCUGUGCCGGGAGACUGGAGCGGCUCCUGGCUCCGCGCAGGCAGGGCCCCCAGAGACAGCUCAUGCAGCAGAUCCGCAGCCCCGGGGCCCUCAGGCACCGCCGCGGCUGCCGCCCUCGCUCAGUCCCGAGCGCGUCCACCCUGGCCAGCCAGCUGCCCCCGCUGAACCUGCGCCGGGCGCUCCGGCUCUCCGUUCGGGCCCCAGCCAACCCCGCGGGCUCAGGCUCCCAGUUCCUGUCCCAGCCUGCGCCGGCUCCAGCGCCCCCGGCUCUCCAGCUGCUCUUCCCGACUCCUAUCCUUGGCCGCCCCCAGCGCGGAACCGACCCGCGACCCUACCGCCAACAUCGCGGGUCUCGCCUCUCGCAGCCUUUUUGGCGUCCGCGCCUCAGCGUUGAAGCCAGGGCCCCUCGUGAGCUCGGCG